AAUCGCCAAGGACCGCCGCCUGCCUGAGCAGCCCGGGGUGUCUGUGCCUCCGGAGCCCGAGAACCUGGGACCCAGGCCAGCCAGAGCUAAUUUCUAUCUCCCAGCAUGGAGGAUGACGGCAGCCUGCUCCCUGAGGACGAGCUUUUGGCCGAUGCCCUUCUUUUGGAAGAUGAAAGAGAUGAAUUAGAGGAUCCGGAGUUUGACAUCAAAUGUCUUCUACAGGAAGCUGAGGAUGACGUGGACCCGGGACACAGCAGCUCAGUGAAAGAACUAGAUACUGAUGCUGAUAAAUUGAAGAAGAAAACAGCUGAGGACAGAACGCAGGCAUUUCACCUGCGGCAGAACCUGAGCGCCCUGGAUAAGAUGCAUGAGGAGCAAGAGCUUUUCACUGAGAAGAUGAGAGGGGAGCUGCGCGCCUGUCGGCAGAGGCGGGACCUGAUCGACAAGCAGCAGGAGGCUGUGGCAGCCGAGAUCGCCACAGAGGAAGAGGCGGGCAACAUGGCCGCUGUGGGCCGCCUCCAGGCCGUGUCCAGACGCCUGUUUGCAGAGCUGGAGAACGAGAGAGACCUGCAGUCGAGGACUGAGGCCGUGCUGAAGGAGAGCGAGAACACCAUGUGGCACAUCGAGAUCCAGGAGGGGCGACUCGAGGCCUUCCGGACAGCUGACCGUGAGGAGGUGGAGGCCACGGGGCGGCGGCUCCAGGUGCGCGCAGCCGAGCAGCUCUGCAGAGAGCAGGAGGCCCUGGGGAAGGUGGAGCGGAACCGACUGCUGAGGAUCAGGAAGUCCCUGAACACCCAGAAGGAGCUCGGGCUCAGGCACCAGAAGCUGCUGGAGGACGCCCGGAAGAACCACAAGGUUGCCGUGCGGUUCCUGAAGGCCUCCCUGGGAAGAAUCCGAGAGCAAGAGAAGAAGGAGGAGAUGGAGUGCCACGAGUACAUGAGGCGACGCAUGGAUGCGGUGGUGGCGCUGAAGGGCAGCAUCUCCGCGAACCGGGACACACUGCGGAAGUUCCAAGCAUGGGACCGUGCCAAGGCAGAGCUGGCGGAGCAGAGGGUCCAGGCUGAGAAGAAGGCGAUUCUGGCCCAGGGCAGGGAUGCAUUCAGGCACCUUGUCCACCAGCGCCGGCGCCAGGAGCUGGAGGCCCAGAAGAGGGCCUUUGAGGAGGAGCAGAAGCUCAGAAAGCAGGAGAUCAUCAGUCGGAUUCUGAAAGAGGAGGCUGAGGAGGAAAAGAGGAAGAAACAGCAUCCCCCCACCAGUGCCAGGCACCGGCUGACCCUGAGGGACAAGACCUGGAACUACAUUUCUGACUUUUGCAAGAAGACCACAGUCCCAACCAACACGUACACACUGGACUACGAGGCUGCUGCAGGCCCCGGGCCCUCUCGGUUGCUGGAAGUCGUUUCCAGUGAGCUUAUCCAGGGGGACCCCGGGGCCAGCUCAGAGGAGGAAACGUUAGCUGAGCCCGAGAUCUCUGGGCUUUGGAAUGAAGACUACAAGCCAUACCAGGUGCCCAAGGAGGACGUGGACCGAAAGCCCGUGGGCGGGACAAAGAUGGACAAGGACAUCCUGGAGCGCACGGUGGAGCGGCUGCGGAGCAGGGUGGUCCACAAGCAGGUGGUGUGGGGGCGUGAGUUCCAAGGACGCCCCUUCAACAGCAAACCGGAGCUCCUCCACUUCCAGGACUUUGAUAUUGGCAAAGUGUACAAGAAAAAGAUCACGUUGGUAAACACCACCUACACGAUCAACUACUGCAAGCUGGUGGGCGUGGAGGAGCACCUCCGGGACUUCAUCCACGUUGACUUUGACCCCCCUGGCCCCCUGUCAGCCGGAAUGUCCUGUGAAGUGCUUGUCACCUUCAAGCCGAUGAUAAACAAGGAUCUAGAAGGAAAUAUCUCAUUUUUGGCUCAGACGGGCGAGUUUUCAGUUCCACUGAAAUGUUCAACAAAGAAAUGUUCGCUGUCCCUCGACAAGGAGCUCAUUGACUUCGGCAGCUACGUGGUAGGAGAGACCACGUCUCGGACCAUCACGCUGACCAACGUUGGGGGCUUGGGCACGACUUUCAAGUUCCUGCCAGCUUCAGAGCCCUGUGAGAUGGACGACUCCCAGUCUGCCCUGAAAUUAAGCAGUCUCCUGACCUACGAAGAUAAAAGCUUGUAUGACAAAGCCGCCACCAGCUUCUCUGAGCAGCAGCUAGAGGGCACGGAGUCCUCCCAGGCGGACAUGCAGAGCCGGAAGGAGCUGGAGAAGCUGGACAAGGAGCAGGAGGAGGAGCAGCCCGCAGAACCAGAGAGAUUAACCACAGUGAUACCUCCCAGCGAAGAGCAGACGGAGAUCACGCUGGGGGAGGUAACAGAAGGGGAAAUUGGCCCCUUCAGCUCCAUCAAGGUGCCCAUCGUCUUCACUCCGGUCGUCCCAGGCGACGUCCAAGCCAGGUUCAAAGUCACGUUUAAGAACCCCCAGUGCCCCACGCUGCAUUUCAGGGUCGUGGGCGUGGCCAUCGAUGUGCCGGUCUGGGUGCCGAAGCCCAGCGUGGACCUGAAGAUCUGCAUGUAUGACCGGCUCUACCAGGACUCUGUGCUCGUGCACACGCGGUCGAAAGCUGCCCUGCGCCUGAAGUUCGAGGUGUGCAAGGAGCUGAGGGCCCACCUGGAGCUCCUGCCCAAGACAGGCUAUAUCCAGGCACAGUCGUCCUACUCCGUGCAGCUCAAGUUCCUGCCGCGACACUCCCUCCCGGAGGACGCAGGGAGGUAUUUUGACAAGGAGACCCGAGUCCUGGAGGCCCCGAUGACCAUAUGGGUUGCCGACCAGAACAAGCCAGUGGGAUUCACCGUGCAUGCCAUUGUCACCACCUCGGACCUGGAGCUCAGUCCCUCGGAGGUGGAUUUUGGCUACUGCACCAUCUAUGAGGCCAUCAGGACGGAAAUCAGCCUCCACAACCACUCGCUCCUGCCCCAGGAGUUCGGGUUCGUCAGGCUUCCCAAGUUUGUGGACGUCCAACCCAACGAUGGGUUUGGGACGAUCCUGCCCCUGGAAACGCUGCAGUUCUGUGUGAUCUUCCAGCCCACCAAGGCCGAGGAACACAGAUUCCAACUGACCUGCAAGUCUGAGAUCAACCGGUGCUUCAAGCUGUCUUGCCGGGCUGUAGGCGUCCACCCACCCCUGGAGCUGUCCCACUACCAGAUCAAGUUUGCCGCCACGGCCCUAUACGACACCUCCGUGGCUACAGUGUACGUCAUCAACUCUCACCUGAGCAUGAGCUCACCGACCCACUCCAAGCCCCGCAUUGGCUCAGAGGACGCCUCUCCCAUGGGGCCCACGUCUUUCGAGUUCCUGCUGCCCCCAGACUCGCCUAUCACCAUCUCGCCCUCAGUGGGGACCGUGUGGCCAGGAAAGAGGUGCCUGGUCCAGGUGGCCUUCCGGCCAGUGCUGCCCGAGAAGCUGAUCCGCCAGGAAGCCCUCCCACUCCUGAACAAAGAAAUGGAGACCAAAUCUUUCCGAAAGAAUAUGGCCCCCCAGAGGAAGGACCUGCAUGGACUGUCAUUCUCCGUUCUUCGAGCACAGAACCGCGACAAGCUGUUCAAAGUCUCUGUCCCCCACGUCCUGGAGAUGCGGAAGCGGGAGCUGAGGCCCAGUUCCGACGAGUACCAGGCCGCCCGAGCCACCCUGCUCAGAGCGUUCCAGGCGAAGUUUGACACAUUUGUAGUUCCCUGUGUUGUUGCCAGUGGCGACAUCAAAGACAGGAAGGGGUCAGAACCCCUGAGCUUCAGCCCCCACAACACCCUGUACCUGGAGCUGUGGUGCCCGACGGUGGCACCAUCUGUUGUGGUGACGUCCCAUAAAGGCAAGACCAUCUUUAACUUCGGCGACGUCGCUGUGGGGCACCGCAGUAUCAAGAAGAUCUCCAUCCAGAACGUCUCUCCCGAGGAUCUGGCCCUGGACUUCUCCCUGCUGAACCCCAACGGCCCCUUUGUCCUGCUGAACCACUCCAGCCUGCUGCGUGCAGGUGGGACCCAGGUCCUGGUGCUUUCCUUCUCUCCCCACGAGAGCAUCCUGGCUCAAGAAACACUGGACAUCAUCACCAAGAGAGGCACGCUCACCCUCACCCUCAUGGGCACUGGCGUGGCGUCCAUGAUCACGUGCUCCAUUGAAGGCAGCGUCCUCAACAUGGGCUAUGUGAUUGCCGGAGAGUCUGUGUCCUCAGGCUUCAAGCUGCAGAACAACUCUCUGCUCCCCAUCAAGUUCUCCAUGCACCUGGACAGCCUCUCCAGCACCCGGGGCCGGGGCCAGCAGCAGCUGCCGCAGUUCCUCAGCUCGCCCUCCCAGAGGACGGAGGUGGUCGGGACGCAGAAUCUCAACGGUCAGAGCGUGUUCAGCGUGGCCCCCGUCAAGGGCGUCAUGGACCCCGGGAAGACACAAGACUUCACUGUCACCUUCAGCCCCGACCACGAAAGCCUCUACUUCUCCGACAAGCUCCAGGUGGUGCUCUUUGAAAAGAAAAUCUCCCACCAGAUCCUGCUGAAGGGUGCCGCCUGUCAGCACAUGAUGUUCGUGGAGGGCGGCGACCCCCUGGACGUGCCCGUGGAGUCUCUGACAGCGAUCCCUGUAUUUGACCCCAGGCACAGAGAGGCCAGCUCCCGGCCAGGCCCUCUCUCUCCAGAAGCUGAGGAGCUGAGGCCCAUCCUGGUGACCCUGGACUACAUCCAGUUUGACACAGACACGCCAGCCCCACCUGCCACCCGAGAGCUGCAGGUGGGCUGUAUCCGGACCACCCAGCCAUCUCCAAAGAAGACCGUUGAGUUCAGCAUAGACAGCGUCGCAUCCCUGCAGCACAAGGGUUUCUCUAUUGAGCCCUCCAGGGGCUCCGUGGAGCGCGGCCAGACGAAGACCAUCAGCAUCUCCUGGGUGCCACCUGCGGACUUUGAUCCAGACCACCCACUCAUGGUGUCGGCCCUGCUGCAGCUAAGGGGGGAUGUGAAGGAGACCUACAAGGUCAUCUUUGUAGCCCAGGUGUUGACUGGCCCCUAAGCCUCUGCACAGAGCACCCUCGGGCCCUCCUGUCCACCCUCAAAGCCCUCCCCAGGCUGAGGGCCAGGUCAUACUACCCUAGAGCCUGGGACCUGGCCAUCCUCUGCCAGAUUCCAAUAGGCCGCCCUCCACAUGGCGCCACGGCCACUUCCUGCUGCCCUGGACCCCGCAAGCCCAGGGACAUCCAAGAGCACCCCUCCUGAGACCCCAGACUCAGAAGCAGCGAGAAGGCCAGGCCAGCCCUCAGCCAUCCUAGCCAGACCCCCUCAGAGCCCCCAGCCCCCAGGAGAGCCCUCCACAGCCUGUCAAUAAAUUUUUUGUAGGCCAACA